AGGACUUGAGUUGCCUUGUCUGGUAUCCUUAUGCAGAAUGAACUGAAAUAAUCAUCAAUCUGAAAAGCUACUCUUAAACAGAGUCUCACUCUGUCAACCAGGCUGGAGUGCAGCAGCACGAUCUCAGCUAACUGCAACCUCUGCCUCCCAGGUUCAAGCGAUUCUCCUGCCACAGCCUCCGGAGUAGCUGGGACUACAGGCAUGUGCCACCACGCUGAUCUAAUUUUUGUAUUUUUAGCAGACAUGGGGUUUCACCUUUUUUGGCCAGGCUGGUCUCAAACUCCUGACCUCAAGUGACCUGCCCACCUCAGCCUCCUAAAGUGUUGAAAUUACAGGCACGAGCCAUAGUACCCAGCCGAAUCACUCUUUUAUUUUUUUUUACAUCACUCUUACGAGUCAUCAAAAACAACUAUAAAAGACUUGCUUCAACACCAGGAAGAACAUGAAAGGGUGACUCAUAAUUCCCAGCAGCAGUGCCAGUUCAUGUGCUGGGAUUCUGACCACAAGCCUAACAAUCAGGUCAGGGAGUCAGAUUUCUGUUGGAUUUAGAAAAGCAUCUAUGUGUUUAUGAAAGAAACCCACUGGAUUUUUAAUAGUUCUGCAGCUCUUGGAGGCUCUACAUCUACCCUUUCUCCCCAGCCAAGAGCAUGGCUAUGGGAGAAGGAAGGCAGGCAGCAGGCAGGGCAGUGUGCCCGCCCUCUCUUUCUGGAGUAUAAAAGGAGUUGUGAGAGGCUUGGGUCACCAUUUGGUGAGCUGAGGGUGAAGCUACAAAGGUUGAAGCGUUCUUCAGACGACUCUACCUGAGGGUGAAGCUACAAAAAUUGAAGCGUUCUUCAGACGACUCUACCUGAAGAAAGAACCCUGCUACAGAGAGGGCAAUUCUGUGGUGUUCUUGGUCACACAUUUAUGGAGUUUCUGAAGGGCAGUGGAGAUUACUGCCAGGCACAGCACGACCUCUAUGCAGACAAGUGAACUGUAGAAACUGAUUACUGCUCCACCAAGAAGCCCCCAUAAGAGUGGUUAUCCUGGACACAGAAGUGUUGAAUUGAAAUCCACAGAGCAUUUUACAAGAGUUCUGACCUGGAUGGGGUAAACCUCAGUGCACUUCUUUUCUGUUGGCCUCAGUAUUACUGGAUUGAAGAAUUGCUGCUUCUUGUUAGGAGGUUCAUUUCACUUAUCAUUACUUACAACUUCAUACUCAAAGCACUGAGAAUUUCAAGUGGAGUAUAUUGAAGUAGACUUCAGUUUCUUUGCAUCAUUUCUGUAUUCAAUUUUUUUAAUUAUUUCAUAACCCUAUUGAGUGUUUUUUAACUAAAUUAACAUGGCUCGAAUGAACCGCCCAGCUCCUGUGGAAGUCACAUACAAGAACAUGAGAUUUCUUAUUACACACAAUCCAACCAAUGCGACCUUAAACAAAUUUAUAGAGGAACUUAAGAAGUAUGGAGUUACCACAAUAGUAAGAGUAUGUGAAGCAACUUAUGACACUACUCUUGUGGAGAAAGAAGGUAUCCAUGUUCUUGAUUGGCCUUUUGAUGAUGGUGCACCACCAUCCAACCAGAUUGUUGAUGACUGGUUAAGUCUUGUGAAAAUUAAGUUUCGUGAAGAACCUGGUUGUUGUAUUGCUGUUCAUUGCGUUGCAGGCCUUGGGAGAGCUCCAGUACUUGUUGCCCUAGCAUUAAUUGAAGGUGGAAUGAAAUACGAAGAUGCAGUACAAUUCAUAAGACAAAAGCGGCGUGGAGCUUUUAACAGCAAGCAACUUCUGUAUUUGGAGAAGUAUCGUCCUAAAAUGCGGCUGCGUUUCAAAGAUUCCAACGGUCAUAGAAACAACUGUUGCAUUCAAUAAAAUUGGGGUGCCUAAUGCUACUGGAAGUGGAACUUGAGAUAGGGCCUAAUUUGUUAUACAUAUUAGCCAACAUGUUGGCUUAGUAAGUCUAAUGAAGCUUCCAUAGGAGUAUUGAAAGGCAGUUUUACCAGGCCUCAAGCUAGACAGAUUUGGCAACCUCUGUAUUUGGGUUACAGUCAACCUAUUUGGAUACUUGGCAAAAGAUUCUUGCUGUCAGCAUAUAAAAUGUGCUUGUCAUUUGUAUCAAUUGACCUUUCCCCAAAUCAUGCAGUAUUGAGUUAUGACUUGUUAAAUCUAUUCCCAUGCCAGAAUCUUAUCAAUACAUAAGAAAUUUAGGAAGAUUAGGUGCCAAAAUACCCAGCACAAUACUUGUAUAUUUUUAGUACCAUACAGAAGUAAAAUCCCAGGAACUAUGAACACUAGACCUUAUGUGGUUUAUUCCUUCAAUCAUUUCAAACAUUGAAAGUAGGGCCUACAUGGUUAUUUGCCUGCUCACUUUAUGUUUACAUCUCCCACAUUCAUACCAAUAUACGUCAGGUUUGCUUAACCAUUGAUUUUUUUUUUUUUUUACCAAGUCUUACAGUGAUUAUUUUACGUGUUUCCAUGUAUCUCACUUUGUGCUGUAUUAAAAAAACCUCCAUUUUGAAAAUCUACGUUGUACAGAAGCACAUGUCUUUAAUGUCUUCAGACAAAAAAGCCUUACAUUAAUUUAAUGUUUGCACUCUGAGGUGCAACUUAACAGGGAGGGCCUGAGAAAAGAAUGGGAGGGGGCUAUUAAUUAUUUUUAGCAAAAUGUUGCCUUUGUCUUGUGCAAACAUGUAGAAUAUGCUCUUUAAUUUAGUAAAAUAUUUUUUUAAAAGGUAGAGAUGCUUUGUUAUUGUAAUCAUAAACUUCCUGAAAUUCUUGUAAUUUUUUUCCCAUACUUAUCAGAAGUGUGUUUACCAACUUAUUUUUGUUUGAAAGUGUGAUUUUUUUUUUCCUUCCCAACCUCUCUUGCAAAAAAAGAAAUGGGUUUCUGCUAAUGAAUUGAGCAGACAUCUAAUAUUUUAUAUGCCUUUUGAGCUGUGUAACUUAAUAUUUGGAUACUUGACAAUUUGUUUUAUUAUGUAAUUGAUAAAAUGGUGAUGUGUAUUAAUGUUAGUUCAACCAUAUAUUUAUACUGUCUGGGGAUGUGUGGUUAUAGUUCUGUGGGAGAAAUAAUUUUGUCAGUGUUCACCAGCUUGUAAAAACUUAGUGCGAGAGCUGAAACAUCUAAAUAAAUAAUGACAUGCAUUUAUCAUCAUUGAGAUUGGUUUGCUUAAAAUUAACUUAUUUUGUAGAAGACAAAAUGAAUUGCACUUCACUUAAUGUGUGUCCUCAUCUUUUUACAAAUAAAUGAAGGAUUAUAAAUGAUGUCAGCAUUUUAGUAAACUUUUAGACAAAAUUUGUUAGGGUCAUUCAUGAAAACUUUAAUACUAAAAGCACUUUCCAUUAUAUACUUUUUAAAGGUCUAGAUAAUUUUGAACCAAUUUAUUAUUGUGUACUGAGGAGAAAUAAUGUAUAGUAGAGGACAGCCUUGGUUUGUAAAGCUCAGUUCCACUAGUUCAUGGUUUUGUGCAACUUCUGAGCCUCAGUUUUCUCCUUUGCAAAUUAAUAAUUACAUACCUUUAUAGAUUUUGAAAUUAAUUUAAAUAUUAGUAUUUGGUACAUGAAGGCUUAAUGUUAAGUUUCCUUUAAUGAUCCACAAUAAUCCCUUUGAUCACGUUAAUCUAAAUCUAGAUGUCUUUGUCUAAUUUUUUUUGAAUAGCAGUUAUAAAUGUAAAGGACUCAAAGUUUAAGUAAAAAGUGAUACUCCACCUUGUGUUUCAAAGAAUUUAGUUCCACCUCUUCAUACCAGUUUAACACUUAAUAUAUUUCAUUGGAUUUUAGACAGGGCAAAAGGAAGAACAGGGGCCUCUGGAGGCCCUUGGUUAUUUAAAUCUUGGAUUAUUUGUGAUAGUAAUCACAAAUUUUUGGCUAAUUUUUAACCUGAGGUUUUGUUUUUUUUUUAAAGGAAAUGCAGCCUAGUCUUGAGAACAUAAUUUUAUAUAAUCAAUUACUAAAUGUUAAACUAUUACCACACAGCCCAUAAAACAGCAUUUGCGUUUAUUGAGAGAGAGGAUGUGCCAUCAUGAUUAAUGAAAACUAUCUUUUGAGUUUGAAAAGAAAUUAAUUUGCAGUGUUUGGAUUGUAUAUAUGGUGCUAAAAAUAAAUUAAUUUACUUUAUAAACCUUAUCUGUACAUUAUACGAUGUGAUGAAAUUUGCUUUUUAUCCAAAUAUUUUGUAUCUUGUAAAUAUGGCUAAUUAUAGGAAUGCCUAUAAUACAUCUUAGAUUCCUUAUAUCUAAUAAGAGUUCAAAGAGUUAUGAGUUGAAGUCUUGAAUGCAGGAAACUAUCUGAUAGUGUUCUAAAAUUUGGUUACUUGGGUUUGGAUACCCUUAGUGGGAUGAUGUAAAUAGAGGCUAGCUACCUAGGCUUGUCUAUAGCAACCAUAAUGUUGAUGUAAGUAAUGCGGUUACUGAAUCAUAAGAAAAUGCCAUCUCUUUUUAGUUGAAGGAAAACUCUGGAAGUAGGUGCCAUUGGUCAUUCUGCAGUGCACUGCAACCAUUGUUUCCCCUAGUGCCCUCUUUUCCCUAGGGCAUUGCUCUCCUAUUCCCACGCCUUAACACAGCUCUAUACCUAGAAGCAGCCAGCCCAGGCAUGCAGUCACAUUUAAUCACAUCCCCCUUCUAGAGUGCUUCAAAAUGAUGUAGUCCCUCAACUUGGCUAAAGAAUCUCAAUCUCUUGAAAUUUAUUUUUUUAAUGUCAUAUUCAUCUGGUAAAUAUCUACUGUUUGCCAGGCAUUUAAGAAUAUGGCAAAGAACAUAAAAGAUGGUGUCACCAGAUUUUGGUCACCAAUGAGUACCCGACCCGUUGCCAUGAUUAAGAGAGAAUGCUUUCUAUUGGAGUUUCAGGAAAUAUAAUUUGAGAAUACUUUAAAGGGAAGUGGAAGUAUAAGUGAAUGAUAUUUUUCUUUUACAUGUAAACAAUGAAGUUAUUUCAAAGUUAAGUUUUAAACAAAAUACAUGAAGUAGUGUCUGCCAUACAUGUUAAUAUUCUACAUUCUUGCUUCCUUAAAUUAAUAUGUUUGUGUGUAUAUAUGUGCCUCACACCUGAAUUGAAAAUUAAAGACUGGUUUAAAAGUGGUUUAAAAGUGACAUUUAAUGUUUCUCCAUUACGUUUGGGGUAACCAGCCUAAGUGGAAUCUUGGAAGGAAAGUAAGGGAAAAACUUGUAUUUGCCUUCAAUGAAUUAAACCAGUGAUAUGUGUUAACGUAUGAAUGAAAGGAUUGAUGGUGAUUUUAUAAUUAUAUAUAUUGCCGCAGUAACCAGUUAAUAAAUUGAUAGCUACCAUUUA